GCUCACUUCUCUCUCCCUGUGAAGAGCGUGGGGGACUCCGCGCAGAGGUCGACAGAGGUUGAGGCAGGGCCAGGAGCCAUGAUGGACACAGAGGGGCAGUAGAGGCUGCAGGCGUCUCCACAACCCCAGCGCAGAGGGGCCCGGGCCAGGGCCACAGGGAGCCAUGGAGAGCUUCAUGGAGUCGCUGAACAGGCUGAAGGAGAUCCACGAGAAGGAAGUCCUGGGCCUGCAGAACAAGCUUCUGGAACUGAACUCAGAGAGGUGCCGGGACGCCCAGAGGAUCGAGGAGCUCUUCUCCAAGAACCACCAGCUCCGGGAACAGCAGAAGACACUGAAGGAGAACCUGCGGGUGCUGGAGAACAGGCUGCGGGCCGGCCUGUGCGACCGCUGCAUGGUCACCCAGGAGCUGGCCAGGAAGCGGCAGCAGGAGUUCGAGAGCUCCCACCUGCAGAACCUGCAGCGCAUCUUCAUCCUCACCAACGAGAUGAACGGGCUGAAGGAAGAGAACGAGACCUUGAAGGAGGAGGUGAAGCGGCUUCGGGGCCUGGGAGACAGGCCCAAGCCCCGGGCCAAGGAGGGCACCUCGGACCCCCCCUCACCCCUGCUGCUCCCCUCCCCUGGUGGCUGGAAGGCCAUCACAGAGAAGCCACCGGGAGGCCACGAGGAGGCUGAGGAAGACCACCAGGGCGUGGGCCUACGGGGAGAAGAAAAGCCAGCAGGGCACAGGACAUCUCCAGUGGCCAAAAUCUCCCCAGGGGCCACCCUGCCUGAGUCGCGAGCCCCAGACAUGAGCCCCCAGCGCAUCUCCAACCAGCUGCACGGGACCAUUGCCGUGGUGCGGCCUGGGUCCCAGGCUUGCCCUGCCGACCGAGGCCCCGCCAAUGGGACGCCCCCACCACUGCCCGCCAGGAGCAGCCCACCCAGCCCAGCGUAUGAGCGUGGCCUCUCCCUGGACAGCUUCCUGCGGGCCUCCCGGCCCUCCGCCAUGACCCAUGAGGCCCCGAAGCUCUCCCCGAAGGUGGACCGGCUCUGCCUCCUAAACCGCCCCCUGUCCCUGCACCUUCAGAGCCCCCACAGCAGCCCCCUGGCCCCUGCUGCAGCCCCCAGCGACCCCCGGCUCCAGGACCUGAAGGCCAGAGAAGCAGAGGCCUGGGAGGAGCCCACAGAACUGCUGGGGCUGCCCAGUGCCCUGGCGGGCAUGCAGGACCUUCGCCUGGAGGGGGCACUGCACCUGCUCCUGGCCCAGCAGCAGCUGCGGGCUAGGGCCAGGGCAGGCAGUGUCAGGCCAAGGGGCCAGCCCACACCCGGGGAGAUGCUGCCCUCCCUACCAGUCGGCUCAGACUCUGAGGGCCCUGAGAAUGAGGGGACCAGGGCAGCUCUGGCCGCAGCAGGCCUGUCUGGAGGGCGGCACACACAGCCUGCAGGCCCGGGCCGCGCCCAGAGGACAGAGGCUGCAGCCACGCAGGACUGUGCCCUAGACAAGCCCCUGGACCUCUCGGAGUGGGGCCGGGCCCGGGGCCAGGACACUCCCAAGCCGGCCGGCCAGCAUGGGUCACUCAGCCCUGCCGCUGCCCACACUGCCAGCCCCGAGCCACCCACCCAGUCCGGACCCCUGACUCGCAGUCCCCAGGCACUCAGCAAUGGCACCAAGGGGACCAGAGUGCCAGAGCAGGAGGAGGCUUCCACUCCCAUGGACCCCUCACGCCCACUUCCAGGGUCCCAGCUCAGCCUGUCCUCUCCAGGCAGUACAGAAGAUGAAGACACAGGGAGGCCUCUGCCACCUCCCCACCCACAGCCGCCUCCCCACCCACAGCCGCCUGACCUGGACGGCCACCCAGAGCCCAGCAAGGCUGAAGUGCUGAGACCAGAGUCCGACGAACUGGAUGAGACAGACACCCCAGGCAGCGAGGUGGGCCUGAGCUCCCAGGCGGAGGCCACUACGAGCACGACCGGGGAGGGGCCUGAGUGCAUCUGCACCCAGGAGCACGGGCAGGGUCCACCACGGAAGAGGAAGCGGGCCUCGGAGCCUGGGGACAAAGCCUCCAAAAAGCCAUCCAGAGGGAGAAGGAAACUGACAGCCACUGAGGGGCCCGGGAGCCCAAGGGACGCCGAGGACCACAGUCCCUCCCCCAACAGCAGCCCCUGGGAGGAGACCUAGCCAGCCUGCACCAGGGUCCACAGCGAGCCCGGGGCAGCCCUCCACCUGCCCACCAGGGCCUGGAGAGGGCACACCAUCCAACCAGCAGGCAGCCCUGCACAGAACCCUGGGAGAAGACCUAGCCAGCCUCAGCUGAACCCACAGUGAGCCCAGGGCAGCUCUCUGCCUGCUCACCACAGCCUGGAGAGGGCACACCACCCAACCAGCAGGCAACCCCGAAGAGCCGGUGACGGGCACAUCCUGGCCCACUUCAAGAGGGGCUGGAGGACCGAGAGGGGUCUCAGGCUGGCGAUUCACCCCGUCUCCACCCACCUGGGAAAUGCUCUGCGGCCCCUCCCACAGCCCAGCACCUGCUCCCUGAGGGGUGUGGGGACUGGAGGCGGGAUCACUCAGGCUCCAGCCCAGCCCUACCCCUGCUGUGCACUGCAGCCGUUCCCAGGCAGUGCCCACGCUCUGGGAGGCAACGGACCACUCGGACCCCCACCCCUGCCCGCCAAGCUCCAAGCACAAUCUUGGACGCCCCCUCGUGGGCUGACAGCAAACAGAUGUCUGGCAGUGAGGGUGGAGGGAGACAGUGGGCGGCAGCACCCUCGAAGACCGGGUCCCCUGAGUGACGGAGAAUAAACACUUGAAGAACCGUG